GCCGAGCCCCGCCGGAGGGAGGCGGCUCCGCGCGGGGCCCGCCGCCCGCGCCGCCGCCACCGAAACCCGGCCGCGGCGCGCCCGACCUUCUGCGCCGGCUGCCGCGGCCGCCCUCGCCGCGCUCCCGCCCCGGCCGCUGCCCCUGCCCGCCCCGCUCGCCCCGCGCACCCCAACCCGGGGAGGGGCUCCCACGACCCCGGGCGCGCGCGCUUGGGGGCGCGCCAGGGACUCCAGGGUCCCUUGCCCCGCGCCGCUUCUCCCUCCUCCCUCUUUCUUCGGGCAGCCUCCCCACCACCCCACUUCAGCCUCCCCCACUCUUGCCGCCUCCAUAUCAUCAAGCUCUGGUGGCGCCUGGGGGGCUUUUCGGAUCGGCAGGAUGUACCCCCAGGGAAGGCACCCGACCCCGCUCCAGUCCGGCCAGCCCUUCAAGUUCUCGAUCUUGGAGAUCUGCGACCGCAUCAAAGAAGAAUUCCAGUUUCUUCAGGCUCAAUACCACAGCCUCAAGCUAGAAUGUGAGAAGCUGGCCAGCGAGAAGACGGAAAUGCAGCGACAUUAUGUCAUGUAUUAUGAGAUGUCGUACGGGCUCAACAUUGAAAUGCAUAAGCAGGCGGAGAUUGUGAAGCGUCUGAGCGGUAUCUGCGCUCAGAUUAUCCCCUUCCUGACCCAGGAGCAUCAGCAGCAGGUGCUCCAGGCCGUAGAACGCGCCAAGCAGGUCACCGUGGGGGAGCUGAACAGCCUCAUCGGGCAGCAGCAGCUCCAGCCGCUGUCCCACCACGCACCCCCUGUGCCCCUCACCCCCCGCCCAGCCGGGCUGGUGGGCGGCAGUGCUACGGGGCUGCUUGCUCUGUCUGGAGCCCUGGCUGCCCAGGCUCAGCUGGCGGCGGCUGUCAAGGAGGACCGUGCGGGCGUGGAGGCCGAGGGGUCCAGAGUGGAGAGAGCCCCGAGCAGGAGUGCAUCUCCCUCGCCCCCUGAGAGUCUCGUGGAGGAGGAGCGACCGAGUGGCCCUGGUGGUGGCGGGAAGCAGAGAGCAGAUGAGAAGGAGCCAUCAGGACCUUAUGAAAGCGACGAAGACAAGAGUGAUUACAAUCUGGUGGUGGACGAGGACCAACCCUCAGAGCCCCCCAGCCCGGCUACCACCCCCUGCGGAAAGGUACCCAUCUGCAUUCCUGCCCGUCGGGACCUGGUGGACAGUCCAGCCUCCUUGGCCUCUAGCCUUGGCUCACCGCUGCCUAGAGCCAAGGAGCUCAUCCUGAAUGACCUUCCCGCCAGCACUCCUGCCUCCAAAUCCUGUGACUCCUCCCCGCCCCAGGACGCUUCCACCCCCGGGCCCAGCUCGGCCAGUCACCUCUGCCAGCUUGCUGCCAAGCCAGCACCUUCCACGGACAGCGUCGCCCUGAGGAGCCCCCUGACUCUGUCCAGUCCCUUCACCACGUCCUUCAGCCUGGGCUCCCACAGCACUCUCAACGGAGACCUCUCCGUGCCCAGCUCCUACGUCAGCCUCCACCUGUCCCCCCAGGUCAGCAGCUCUGUGGUGUACGGACGCUCCCCCGUGAUGGCAUUUGAGUCUCAUCCCCAUCUCCGAGGGUCAUCCGUCUCUUCCUCCCUACCCAGCAUCCCUGGGGGAAAGCCGGCCUACUCCUUCCACGUGUCUGCGGACGGGCAGAUGCAGCCGGUUCCCUUCCCCUCGGAUGCACUGGUAGGCGCGGGCAUCCCGCGGCACGCCCGGCAGCUGCACACGCUGGCCCAUGGCGAGGUGGUCUGCGCGGUCACCAUCAGCGGCUCCACACAGCAUGUGUACACGGGCGGCAAGGGCUGUGUGAAGGUGUGGGACGUGGGCCAGCCUGGGGCCAAGACGCCCGUGGCCCAGCUCGACUGCCUGAACCGAGACAACUACAUUCGUUCCUGCAAGUUGCUGCCGGAUGGCCGGAGUCUGAUCGUGGGCGGUGAGGCCAGCACCUUGUCCAUUUGGGACCUGGCGGCGCCCACCCCCCGUAUCAAGGCCGAGCUGACUUCCUCAGCCCCAGCCUGCUACGCCCUGGCCGUCAGCCCCGACGCCAAGGUUUGCUUCUCCUGCUGCAGCGAUGGCAACAUUGUGGUCUGGGACCUGCAGAAUCAGACUAUGGUCAGGCAGUUCCAGGGCCACACGGACGGCGCCAGCUGCAUUGAUAUUUCCGAUUACGGCACUCGGCUCUGGACAGGGGGCCUGGACAACACGGUGCGCUGCUGGGACCUGCGGGAGGGCCGCCAGCUGCAGCAGCAUGACUUCAGCUCCCAGAUUUUCUCCCUGGGCCACUGCCCUAACCAGGACUGGCUGGCGGUCGGAAUGGAGAGUAGCAACGUGGAGAUCCUGCACGUCCGCAAGCCGGAGAAAUACCAGCUGCACCUCCACGAGAGCUGCGUGCUGUCCCUGAAGUUUGCCUCCUGCGGACGGUGGUUUGUGAGCACCGGGAAGGACAACCUGCUCAACGCCUGGAGGACGCCGUACGGGGCCAGCAUUUUCCAGUCCAAGGAGUCGUCCUCAGUCCUGAGUUGUGACAUCUCCAGAAAUAACAAAUACAUCGUGACAGGCUCGGGGGACAAGAAGGCCACCGUGUAUGAGGUGGUCUACUGAGACAUGACCCCCCUUCCUGUACCCGAAGUCCAGACUCCCAGGGGAAUCAGCAGCCAGGACAGACAUCCUAGCAGCCGCCUCCCAGCCCUGCCUAGGAACCGUACAUCCCAUCUGCUCUCUGGCCAACGGCUUCACACCUUCCCCUGCUGCAUGUGGGGGCCGAUGGGCAGGGGACCUCGGUGGAAAUAAAAUGUAUCUAUCACA